CUCGUAUAGACUAGAAACACCUCAGCGUGAACAACAAGCUAGAAACCUUCUCUUUGUUCUUCUUCUCUCUAGAUUAUAUAUACACAUAUAUGUAUAUAUAGAAGAGAUAUGAUAAACAUAGAGGUAGAUAUAUGCUCCAAAUUUAAUUUAAUACAACAUAAAUCAGAGAACAUCUUAUUAAUAAAAAUCAUGAGAAGAAAUGAACCUAGAAAUCAACUAUGAGAAACCAUACAACAGUAGCAAACUUUAUUCUUCUUGGACUGACAGAUGAUCCACAAUUACAGGUGAUUAUUUUUCUUCUCCUUUUUUUCACCUACAUGUUGAGCAUCACUGGGAAUCUAACCAUCAUCACUCUCACCCUACUGGAUUUGCAUCUCAAGACACCCAUGUAUUUCUUCCUCCGAAAUUUCUCAUUUUUAGAAGUCUCAUUCACAACUGUCUACAUUCCCAAAUUUCUUGUUAGUAUGGCAACAGGUGAUAAGACCAUUUCUUACAACGAUUGUGCAGCACAGCUGUUUUUCACUAUUCUCUUGGGGGCAACUGAAUUUUUUCUUCUGGCUGCCAUGUCCUAUGAGCGCUAUGUGGCCAUCUGCAAACCCCUGCAUUACACCACCAUCAUGAGCAGCAGAGUUUGCAGCUUGCUGGUCUUUGCUUCAUGGAUGGCUGGCUUCCUAAUAAUUUUUCCGCCACUCCUGAUGGGUCUCCAGCUUGAUUUCUGUGCAGCCAACACUGUAGAUCAUUUCUUCUGUGAUGUUUCUCCUAUACUGCAGCUCUCUUGCACAGACACUGACAUAAUAGAAUUAAUGAUGCUUCUCUCAGCCAUUUUGACGCUCCUGGUUACACUGGUAUUAGUGAUUCUCUCCUACACAAAUAUUAUCAGGACUAUUCUGAAAAUACCUUCUUCUCAACAGAGAAAAAAAGCAUUUUCUACAUGUUCUUCCCACAUGGUGGUCGUGUCCAUUUCUUAUGGCAGCUGCAUCUUCAUGUAUGUGAAACCCUCAGCAAAAGAAAGAGUGUCAUUAAAUAAAGGGAUAGCUCUGCUCAGCACUUCUGUUGCCCCCAUGUUGAAUCCCUUUAUUUAUACACUGAGAAACAAACAAGUAAAAGAUGUUUUUAAGCACACAGUCAAAAAGAUUGAACUUUUCUCAAUGAAAUGAAUCACUUUAACGAUAUUAUUAAGGUUAUUAGUAAAAUAAAACAAGAAGAGUGGAGUAUGUGCAAAGUUUUUCAAUGUUUGUAUUCAAUAAUAUUACCUCUUUUUUGACUUAUAAUUUUCAUUAUGGCCUUCCUAAUCUCCAAAGCCUAACCUUCACUGCCAUUUCUCCCUCAUGCUGAGAUCACAUAGAAAAGAUAUUUCUUGGUUUUGGUCAAAAUCAUUUGCCUGUUAUUUAUUGCCUCUUUUAUUUCCUCUCAAAAUUCUCUCAGAGGAAGACAAAGUGAGACUUCAGUUUUUCCAUGCUCUUUUCCACUCUUCUGGAAUUCAAGGACCCAAUUUGUCAUAUAUUCUACAUAGAGUUCAGUAGACUACCUAGGUUUGAUCACUUAACGCGUGCAUUAUUGGUGGAUACAAAAGUGAAAUCUGCUUUCUUUCUUAGUGUUUAGUAGAAUCUCGAAGCAAAUCAAUUUAAUGGCAUUUCUUUAAUUACACAGUUUAAUAGCUUCAAUUUUUUUUAACCAGGCUUAGAGAUAUAGUAUACUCUCAGAAAUAAAUGAAAGAAACUUCAGAGAGGUUAAAGCAUUACUGCUAUUGCAGCUAUCAUAUAGAACUUACAGCUAGCAUUUAUUGAUUGCUUACAAUGUGCCAGAUGUUAUUAAAUUUAUUAGUUCCAUCUUCAAAACUCUGUAAGACAGGUAUUUAUAUGCUCCAUUUAUGGAUUAAAAAUAUAAGUCAUAAGGAUUAAAUAAUUUGUUGAUGACAACAAAAAUAAAUACCCAAGGAUGACAAAAAUGAUGCCUUCAUGUCCACUCACCGCUUACACAUUUUUAGCAAAACGAAGUGAAAAUCUCUCUCUGCUCUUAAGUCACUUAGAAUGCAAAAGAACAGUAAGACCUUUGUAGAACAUUCUAUAGAUUUAUGGAUGUCAUAGAUAAAAUUAAGACCUUACAGCUCCACAGAGUACCUUAUUUUUCAAAUUAAGUGGUUUGAACAUUAAAAUUAGAUAUAAUGACUGAUCAUGUGCAGAGUAUUUAAAAACUUUUCCUUUCAAUAGUACCCUAUCUCAGUGUUAUAAGACAAGAAAACUUUUUCUGAAAGACUAAUGUCAGUUUCCUCAAGAAAUAUUUGUCUAUGAUUUAGUUUCCACAUAAGGUAACUGAUAACCUUAUGAAUAAUUCUGACUGGAAGGAUUUAUUUUUCUGACUUAUAAAAUUAUUAUAUACAUUUUAUCUUAAUGUAUUUCCAAGUGUAUAUAACUUUGUCAUAUCCCCAGGCUAGCAAGAAAUUUUAUUUGAAUUUUACAAGCAUUAGUGAGAAGCUUUAAAUAUAUAUAUAUCUAAAUAAAUAUUAACAGGGCACUGAGAAGCUGAGAAGAUUCAAAUAGACUUUUCAAUAGUGGUCAUGUAUGUGUAAAUGGUUUUUAUAAUACUGCAAUACUUUAAGAACAUUUUAUUUGAAAAUAGAAAAUAAAUAUCUAGGGAGUAUUCUUUAACUUUCACUAUUUGGCUUUCUUUGCAUCAGGAAUUUAAGUUUUUUUUUAUUAUUAUACUUUAAGUUCUAGGGUACAUGUGCACAACGUGCAGGUUUGUUAACAUAUGUAUACAUGUGCCAUGUUGGUGUGCUGCACCCAUUAACUUGUCAUUUACAUUAGGUAUAUCUCCUAAUGCUAUCCCUCCCCUCUCCCCCCACCUCACAGCAGGCCCCGGUGUGUGAUGUUCGCCUUCCUGUGUCCAGGUGUUCUUAUUGUUCAAUUCCCACCUAUGAGUGACAACAUGCGGUGUUUGGUUUUUUGUCCUUGCGAUAGCUUGCUGAGAAUGAUGGUUUAUACACAAAUAAUUAUACUUUAUAGAUAAUAACGACACUCAAGAAAAGUUGACUCAAAAUGUUUGGAAUCUGACAAAAAGUCUGAUCUGGAAUAUCUCAGAUUUUCUUCUGAACACUCUUCUCCACAAUUUAAGUUGUUGCCAAAUGCAAAUAUGUAACAUAUUUAUUUUAUAUUUCUAAGUAUUACAUUGCUUACUUUUAAAACUUAUUCUUUAUACAUGAACUCUAAGCUCAGCUCUUUUUAAAGUCUAAUAUAUAGGUAAAUCCAUAAAUCAUUGAAUGUAUAUUAAAAACUUUUUCUCCCCUUUUUUAAUCCAAAAAUGAAUUAUUGACAAUUUUGUGAAAUUCAGAAAUAUACUUAGUAGACUUAACUACUUAGAAUAGAUGGAUUUUUUUCUAUUUCUAGGUUGUUUGUAAGUAGAUAACAGAAAAAGCAAAAGGAAAGAAACCCUAGGCCUAAGUUACGAUGGGAAAAGAUUAGUGAAGAUCAUUUUUUACUUAAUUUGAAAUAAAUCACUAGCAAUCUGAUUUAUUGUGUAAAUACCAGAGAUCAGGGUCCAUUAUAGGCACUUAAAAUUUUUAAAUUGUGCUAGGAUUCUAAAAAAUAUUAAAAUCUCAUUUGUUCACCUGUUUAACUCAUUUCUAAUAUUCAUUUUUCUGGAAGUGAAAAGGAAAAAAAUAACCAACUGUUUUUCACCAGUAUUAGGUUGGCGCAAAAGGAAUUGCAGUUUCACCAUUAAAAGUAAUUAAAAUUUCACCAUUAAAAUUUAAUUUCACCACUAAAAGUAAUGGUGAAAUCACAAUUCCUUUUGUACCAACCUAAUAUAUACUGAGUAAGUAUUAAGACAAGCUAGACUCAAGGUAUGUCAAUUGUCUAUUACAUAGCCUUCCUGCCUUUGAUCUCUAACUCAUCCUCCACAUUGCUAGUAGGAUACUUUCUAAAAUACAAAUCAGUCAUGCCACCACUCUACUAAUACAUUAUUGAUGGUUCUCCGUUGCCUGCAAAAUAAUGACAAAAUUCCCCAAAUAUUUGCAUAACCUGGCCUGUCCAGUUUGGUUUCUUAUCUCUUCCAACUAGUACUUCUAUGAUGUAACCACACUAAACAACUAAGUAUAUUGCAAAACUUGUGUGCUGUCACGUAUAUUGAAUGCCUGCCCAUUGCCCAAAUCUCUGUUAGCUUGCAAAACUUCAAUCAGUUAAAGUUAAUUAACAUGGAGACUUCUGUGGAAGGCUGGUCGACAAGUAUAUGUUAGUCACUUCAUACUCAAAUUUUGUAGUGUUUGUAGUCAACUCUAGAUGGUGCUUAUCAUAGCACAUGUAAUUAACUAUAUUUAUUUCUUGCAACGAACUCUAAAUCUCAUAGUUUUCUACAUUCUCUUCAUCCAAGCCGGUGCCUAGUAAGGAAUAAAUAAAAUAAAUAAGGCAGCAAAUGACAGGAGAUGAGUGAAGUUAAUAUGUUCAUCUAUAAAAUAAGAUUAAAAUGUGGCAUUUGAUAGGGCUUAAUAUAAAAAUGUAAGCCUAGAUUAAGGAUGUCUACUAUAAAAUAAUUAAUAGAUUGGACUUGAUGACAGGCAAUAUGAAAAAAAAAUUAGGUGUUAGAAAACUACAAGUUUACUAUAAAUAUGGAGUGUUUAUGAGCAUUGAAGAGAUAAUUCAAUUGUAUGAUACAAUAAAGUCCCAUUGUAUCAUACAUAUCUCAAAAAUUCUGUUUAGUUUUAUCCUUUAAAAAUCUUUUGAAGUAAAAGAAUAGUCAAUAUUAUCAUAAAUUUAGAAAUUAUGUCAUAUGAGAAAAUAUUUAGGGUACUAAUGACAUGGAGCUUGAGAAAAAAUUGCUUAUAAGAAAAAUAAAUGCUACCUUCAAAUAUUAAGAUUACUGUGUUCUCAAAAAUUAUGGACUUGCUUUUCUUUUUAUAAGUGUAAGUGUGCAACUGGUGUUUAUCAAACAUUCAAUUAGUAAAUAUAUGUAUAUUUUUCAUGGUACAUGCACAUUUAUCAGUUUAUAAUUUAUAUAUAAACAAUAGUAUAAAAUAUUUUGAAAUUUUAAUAGAAAAAUAGGAAUUAAUAAAGGAAAUUAUACAAAAUGAUCAAUAUAUUUUAAUAAUAUAACUUUACAGUAUAACUUUUAAUUUUACUUAUGGUACAAAUAUUAGUUUCAUUUUAAUUCAGCAUACUUUAUUAUACUUGCAAAUACUUAUGUAAUUAUUGUGUGAAAUGAACUGCAAGUCUUAUUACAGUUUAUUUUACCUUGUACUUAGUUAUGUGGGUUGUUGUAGUGCAAAGUUAAUGCUUCACAAUAAUGUGGAUCCAUUUUAAAUGAACUGGAAAUCACAAUAAUUAUUCUUCAAUCCCAUUCAAAUAUGCUUUUUUUUUUGAAAUUGACUACAUUAAUGUUAAUCAGCUGUCUUGAUUUUGCAUUUUUAUGUAAUUUUCUAAAAGCACACAAAUGUUUUAAAAUAUUAAAAUGAUUAUGUUUUCAAGUUUUCUAAUGAGUAGAUGAGUAUUUUUAUAUUUAAUGAGUUUAAAUAAUUUCCAGUAACAAAAAUCGUGGAAAGAAUUUCAAACAGUCAAUUUCCAAAUUUCUCUUUUAAUUCAACUUUCUUUUGAUAAUGGGUUACUUUUUCCCAUAUUUUUAAAACACCAUCUGUUUUGGAACAGAGUAAGGGGGUGAUAUCUUCAAGAAAACAUAUUACUGAUGGAGACCUGUUGUCAUAGGGAAGGGAAAACUAGGCUAUGUCUACUUAUAAAAUAAAAUUCCAUAAUUCUCUUCAAUGUGUCUUUUAAAAUACUUUACAUAAGAAAUUCUGAUUCUGUAUCUGAUACAAGUUUUUAAAUUAUUACUUAGCAUAUCAUCAUACAUUUCUGAUUUGCUUCUCUUCCUUUUUUUUCUUCUCCACCUCCCCUUCCUUCUCCUUUCUCUUCUAACAACCCUUUAAAAAUGUAAAAUACAUCUCAGGAUCUCAGGUGGAAGUCUGUACCAAAACAAUCCUUGGCCUGUGGGCUAUGGUUUGCUGGCCUGUGGAAUAAAUGAUGGCAAAGGGCUAGAGUACAAAGGUAUACCAUUUUAUUUGCAGGUUGUGCCAAUAAAUUCUUGUAUUAUCUAUUAAUCCAUAAACAUUCAUUCCCAAAAUCAAUAACUGGAUAUUUAGUGCCAGAAUUAUUUUUGAUUUAUUCUAGUAAAUGGGCCAUAACUGAAAAGACAGUUGCAAUUGAAUUUACUACCUAAUUUAACUUAUGGGUUCAUUAUCAUCUGCUAAAAUUUAUCUGUGUUAGGAGAGGCAGACAGUUGAGUUCAAUGGGUAUGUGGAUUAAGUCACCACUCCUGCAUCUUUGUUUUUUAAGUCUUUGAUGGUGGCACUAGCUUUGAAGCUUUUCCAAGGAUAUAAUGAUGCUGUCUGUUUAUUAUCUCUUAGUGAGGGAGACCAUAUGGUUUUCCACUUGGCCCUGAAUAUAUGUGUUUUAACUGUAUGCACAGGACAACUUUGCACAUGCACUAGGUUCACUGUAAAACAGACUAGCACAUAAUCAUAACUUAUCAGGAAAAUGUCUCUGACUCCAAUUUCUUCCACUCUUAUAAGUAAACACACUGGCAUUUUAUAGUCAUUGUAAUUAAGCUUAGCUCAGAAAUGAGGUGGAAUAACCUCUGAAAAAUCCAUGUUUCAUUGAUUUCACUGUACGAUUUUCUUGGGAAAGGACCACAUAUCUAUUGAAGGACACUAGCGGAAGAUUUGGAUAUUAAUAUGCAUGACAGUUUUGCAAAGACAACUUUCUUCAUGGGUUCUGGUUCUAUGAAAGGAUUGAAGUCUGUAAUUGAAUAAGGAGCUUUAACUCCAUUAUGAUGGCUAAUUCAUUCUUCCUUUCACUUAUCCUAGAGUUCUUUCAAUUAUAUGGACCAGUUAGAAACCUAAUGAGCUGCCUGUUUAUUUUAGUCCUAGGAACUUCAUAAUCUGUUGUUCACUACUAAAGUGCAUCAUGCAAUAUUGAUAACUACUUCGGCCAUACUGACCAAUAAGUAACCACACUGAAUAUGCUCAUAUCAGUUAAGUGCUAUUACAUAGCCUCUGACUUUCCAUGAUCCAUCAUGUCCACUGAAAUCAGGGAGUUCAUUUUAACAAAAGCAUCUUCCAUCUUCAUUUCAAACCAGUGGUUACAAUACUUUUUAAAGCUGCUAGCAAAUACCCUUGUGAAUAUUUUAAUAUCUUGCCAAAAGAUUUUCCUCUGGGUAUUCUCCAGUUACAUAGCUAAGGGGUAUGUAAGUAAAUUGCAUACAAUAAAGCUGUUCCAUAUUGCAAUUCCUCUAAGUUUUAGAUUUAUAUUUACAUAUAUGAAAUACAUACACACAUAUAUGUAAUUCCCAGUUGGGAUCCUUUCAGAUUUCCAAUCAAUUAACUUUCACAAAAGAUAUCUGGGAAGGAUGUAAAUUUAACCAAUAUUGCUGUAUAAUAAACUGCGAGAUCAGAGCCUACCUUUGUUUUCAGCACCAAGUGACAUGAGGAUUUAAGAGAUAAAUUUAUUUAGGACAGUCAUGGGAACUUCAUGAUUUGCUGAUUAUUGUAUAAUUCAAGAUAAUAAUUAAAGGAUACAACCUUGUAAUUUUCUUUCUUUAAGAUCCUCAAUAUGGAUCUUACCAUGUUAUAGCCUUAUAGCAUGUGCAGUACUUGUAUUUCACAUGCUUAGCACAGUGCUCUUUACCUUAUACAUCUACUUUGAGAAAGCUCAGCCUUAAAUAUAAGCUUCUUUCCAAGUGAUAAUAUUUGAUGCCAUAGACUUGUAAUAUUCCAUUUUCUUAUGGUUGCAGCACUUCUCAGACCUUUCAAGAUGAUAUUAACUAAUUAUAAAUUACCCUUCUUAAGGAUCUAUUUCAUGCAACCACUUGUAGUACCAAAUAUAUCAGUUAUCACUGUUAGGUUGCAAUUCUCCAUGGCAUUUCUACACAUUUAAUAUUAUGCUUGGUCUGGAUUUUUUUUUACAAAGUUGUUUUAAUAUCAUUCAGCCUUGAAAGAUCGAAAUAAUACCUCCCUCCAGGGCAGAAGGGAGAUUUGCUUCCUGACUAGGAUUAUAAAAUAGAUGUCUCCCAGGGUGGCCAGGUUGGGCAGGUUUUCUAGCUAUCUCUUUAAAAUAGUGGGGGUUCCCUAAGUUCAGGAUUUCACAGUUGUGUUACAGACUGAUUGUGUCUGCUCUACCCAUGGAGCCCCCUCUGCAUUGCACCCCCUGGGGACUGGGAGGCAAAGGGAACGAGGAAACAACAGAUGUUGGUGAGGAUGUGGAGAAGUAGGAACACUUUUACACUGUUGGUGGGAGUAUAAAUUAGUUCAACCAUUGUGGAAGACAGUGUGGUGAUUCCUCAAGGAUCUAGAACUAGAAAUACCAUUUGACCCAGCAAUCCCAUUACUGGGUAUAUACCCAAAGGAUUAUAAAUCAUUCUACUAUAAAGACACAUGCACACAUAUGUUUAUUGUGGCACUAUUAGCAAUAGCAAAGACUUGGAACCAACCCAAAUGCCCAUCAAUGAUAGGUUGGAUAAAGAAAAUGUGGUACAUAUACACCAUGGAACACUAUAAAAUAUACAUCCAUAAAAAACGAUGAGUUCAUAUCCUUUGCAGGGACAUGGAUGAUGCUGGAAACUAUCAUUCUCAGCAAACUAACACAAGAACAGAAAACCAAACACCGCAUGUUCUCACUCAUAAGUGGGAGUUGAACAAUGACAGAGAAGAAUUUUAAAUGCAUAUUUCUCAAUGAAACUAGGCAGACUUAAAAGGCUAUAAAUUAUUUAAUUUCAUUUAUAUAAUAUUCUGGUAGAGAUAAAUUUAUAGAGAAAGUAACAUAUCAGUGGUUGCCAGGACUUUGUUGGAGUAAGGAUUAAACGAGGAAGCAUAGGGAAUCUUUGGUUAGGGUAGUAAAAUUAUUCUAUAUAGUAAUGUAAAGAUGAAUACAUAAUGUAGGGAGACCCCCUGAAACUAUUGCUAUGGAAUAAAAGGUGAAAUGCUCCUGAUUAUUGUAAAUACAAAAUUGCAUGCAGGAUUGUGUAAAGACAAUGCCAGGUUGGACUGCCAGAAUGAGCCAACAGCACAUGAUGUGCUUCCCCCUGCAGAGAGCCUACGAACGGACAUGCAGUCAGGGAGGUUUCACAUCACCAAGAUUCCUGUCCCAGAAAAGCAGAUGUUCAUAGCUCUGGGAAUGGAAUGGGACCCUUGUGUAGAGCCUAUAAAUGGACGCAUUGGGGGGGCACCUGUUCAUAUGGAUAAGAUAGGGCUAUAAACGCCCUCAUCUUGCCACAGCUCUUCUAGGCCUCUUUGGGGGUAAGGCAUACUCCCUUCUGAUAUUUUCCGGUCUAACCGGUUGUCUAGCUUCACCUCCUGUUUCUAUGGAUUGUUUGUAACCAGCUUUUGCUGCAACUGUUACUGCUGAUUAAUAACUUGCUAAUCAUAGGUUAUGGAAAGACUGUGUUUCUGUUUUAAGGCUCUGUUAGAAAUUACUGAUGCACACACUAUAUUGUAAACUCUUAUCUCUGUAUACUGUACUUCUGCAUACAGAUGUUAUGUUAAAGAACUACUUCAUCCCCAUGUGACCAUCUCACC